AACAGACAUUGGGUACCAUCGAAUGACUGUCAGAACAGAAAGCUAAGGCAAAGGAGGGAGGAUGCUGUGGUCAUCCUUUCUUGUUUUUUUCUUCUUUAAUGAGGAUAGAGCACAUGUGAGAUUUUACUUUCUACUCCAGUAAAAAUUCUGAAGAAUUGCAUUGGAGACUGUUAUAUUCAACACAUACGUGGAUUCUGUGUUAUGAUUUACAUUUUUCUUUAUUUCAGGGGUUUUUCUCCCUUUGCUUGACACUUCUCUGUCCUGACACCUUGAGAAGAAGGAUGUGUUUGCUUACCCUUCCGCCAUGAUUGUAAAUUUCCUGAGGCCUUCCCAGCCAUGCAGCACUCACUUUCUUAUGCAAGGAGCUAAACAGUGAUUAAAGGAGCAGGAUGAAAAGAUGGCACAGUCAGUGCUGGUACCGCCAGGACCUGACAGCUUCCGCUUCUUUACCAGGGAAUCCCUUGCUGCUAUUGAACAACGCAUUGCAGAAGAGAAAGCUAAGAGACCCAAACAGGAACGCAAGGAUGAGGAUGAUGAAAAUGGCCCAAAGCCAAACAGUGACUUGGAAGCAGGAAAAUCUCUUCCAUUUAUUUAUGGAGACAUUCCUCCAGAGAUGGUGUCAGUGCCCCUGGAGGAUCUGGACCCCUACUAUAUCAAUAAGAAAACGUUUAUAGUAUUGAAUAAAGGGAAAGCAAUCUCUCGAUUCAGUGCCACCCCUGCCCUUUACAUUUUAACUCCCUUCAACCCUAUUAGAAAAUUAGCUAUUAAGAUUUUGGUACAUUCUUUAUUCAAUAUGCUCAUUAUGUGCACGAUUCUUACCAACUGUGUAUUUAUGACCAUGAGUAACCCUCCAGACUGGACAAAGAAUGUGGAGUAUACCUUUACAGGAAUUUAUACUUUUGAAUCACUUAUUAAAAUACUUGCAAGGGGCUUUUGUUUAGAAGAUUUCACAUUUUUACGGGAUCCAUGGAAUUGGUUGGAUUUCACAGUCAUUACUUUUGCGUAUGUAACAGAAUUUGUAAACCUAGGCAAUGUUUCAGCUCUUCGAACUUUCAGAGUCUUGAGAGCUUUGAAAACUAUUUCUGUAAUUCCAGGCCUGAAGACCAUUGUGGGGGCCCUGAUCCAGUCAGUGAAGAAGCUUUCUGAUGUCAUGAUCUUGACUGUGUUCUGUCUAAGCGUGUUUGCGCUAAUAGGAUUGCAGUUGUUCAUGGGCAACCUACGAAAUAAAUGUUUGCAAUGGCCUCCAGAUAAUUCUUCCUUUGAAAUAAAUAUCACUUCCUUCUUUAACAAUUCAUUGGAUGGGAAUGGUACUACUUUCAAUAGGACAGUGAGCAUAUUUAACUGGGAUGAAUAUAUUGAGGAUAAAAGUCACUUUUAUUUUUUAGAGGGGCAAAAUGAUGCUCUGCUUUGUGGCAACAGCUCAGAUGCAGGCCAGUGUCCUGAAGGAUACAUCUGUGUGAAGGCUGGUAGAAACCCCAACUAUGGCUACACGAGCUUUGACACCUUUAGUUGGGCCUUUUUGUCCUUAUUUCGUCUCAUGACUCAAGACUUCUGGGAAAACCUUUAUCAACUGACACUACGUGCUGCUGGGAAAACGUACAUGAUAUUUUUUGUGCUGGUCAUUUUCUUGGGCUCAUUCUAUCUAAUAAAUUUGAUCUUGGCUGUGGUGGCCAUGGCCUAUGAGGAACAGAAUCAGGCCACAUUGGAAGAGGCUGAACAGAAGGAAGCUGAAUUUCAGCAGAUGCUCGAACAGUUGAAAAAGCAACAAGAAGAAGCUCAGGCGGCAGCUGCAGCCGCAUCUGCUGAAUCAAGAGACUUCAGUGGUGCUGGUGGGAUAGGAGUUUUUUCAGAGAGUUCUUCAGUAGCAUCUAAGUUGAGCUCCAAAAGUGAAAAAGAGCUGAAAAACAGAAGAAAGAAAAAGAAACAGAAAGAACAGUCUGGAGAAGAAGAGAAAAAUGACAGAGUCCGAAAAUCGGAAUCUGAAGACAGCAUAAGAAGAAAAGGUUUCCGUUUUUCCUUGGAAGGAAGUAGGCUGACAUAUGAAAAGAGAUUUUCUUCUCCACACCAGUCCUUACUGAGCAUCCGUGGCUCCCUUUUCUCUCCAAGACGCAACAGUAGGGCGAGCCUUUUCAGCUUCAGAGGUCGAGCAAAGGACAUUGGCUCUGAGAAUGACUUUGCUGAUGAUGAGCACAGCACCUUUGAGGACAAUGACAGCCGAAGAGACUCUCUGUUCGUGCCGCACAGACAUGGAGAACGGCGCCACAGCAAUGUCAGCCAGGCCAGCCGUGCCUCCAGGGUGCUCCCCAUCCUGCCCAUGAAUGGGAAGAUGCAUAGCGCUGUGGACUGCAAUGGUGUGGUCUCCCUGGUCGGGGGCCCUUCUACCCUCACAUCUGCUGGGCAGCUCCUACCAGAGGGCACAACUACUGAAACAGAAAUAAGAAAGAGACGGUCCAGUUCUUAUCAUGUUUCCAUGGAUUUAUUGGAAGAUCCUACAUCAAGGCAAAGAGCAAUGAGUAUAGCCAGUAUUUUGACCAACACCAUGGAAGAACUUGAAGAAUCCAGACAGAAAUGCCCACCAUGCUGGUAUAAAUUUGCUAAUAUGUGUUUGAUUUGGGACUGUUGUAAACCAUGGUUAAAGGUGAAACACCUUGUCAACCUGGUUGUAAUGGACCCAUUUGUUGACCUGGCCAUCACCAUCUGCAUUGUCUUAAAUACACUCUUCAUGGCUAUGGAGCACUAUCCCAUGACGGAGCAGUUCAGCAGUGUACUGUCUGUUGGAAACCUGGUCUUCACAGGGAUCUUCACAGCAGAAAUGUUUCUCAAGAUAAUUGCCAUGGAUCCAUAUUAUUACUUUCAAGAAGGCUGGAAUAUUUUUGAUGGUUUUAUUGUGAGCCUUAGUUUAAUGGAACUUGGUUUGGCAAAUGUGGAAGGAUUGUCAGUUCUCCGAUCAUUCCGGCUGCUCCGAGUUUUCAAGUUGGCAAAAUCUUGGCCAACUCUAAAUAUGCUAAUUAAGAUCAUUGGCAAUUCUGUGGGGGCUCUAGGAAACCUCACCUUGGUAUUGGCCAUCAUCGUCUUCAUUUUUGCUGUGGUCGGCAUGCAGCUCUUUGGUAAGAGCUACAAAGAAUGUGUCUGCAAGAUUUCCAAUGAUUGUGAACUCCCACGCUGGCACAUGCAUGACUUUUUCCACUCCUUCCUGAUCGUGUUCCGCGUGCUGUGUGGAGAGUGGAUAGAGACCAUGUGGGACUGUAUGGAGGUCGCUGGCCAAACCAUGUGCCUUACUGUCUUCAUGAUGGUCAUGGUGAUUGGAAAUCUAGUGGUUCUGAACCUCUUCUUGGCCUUGCUUUUGAGUUCCUUCAGUUCUGACAAUCUUGCUGCCACUGAUGAUGAUAACGAAAUGAAUAAUCUCCAGAUUGCUGUGGGAAGGAUGCAGAAAGGAAUCGAUUUUGUUAAAAGAAAAAUACGUGAAUUUAUUCAGAAAGCCUUUGUUAGGAAGCAGAAAGCUUUAGAUGAAAUUAAACCGCUUGAAGAUCUAAAUAAUAAAAAAGACAGCUGUAUUUCCAACCAUACCACCAUAGAAAUAGGCAAAGACCUCAAUUAUCUCAAAGACGGAAAUGGAACUACUAGUGGCAUAGGCAGCAGUGUAGAAAAAUAUGUCGUGGAUGAAAGUGAUUACAUGUCAUUUAUAAACAACCCUAGCCUCACUGUGACAGUACCAAUUGCUGUUGGAGAAUCUGACUUUGAAAAUUUAAAUACUGAAGAAUUCAGCAGCGAGUCAGAUAUGGAGGAAAGCAAAGAGAAGCUAAAUGCAACUAGUUCAUCUGAAGGCAGCACGGUUGAUAUUGGAGCUCCCGCCGAGGGAGAACAGCCUGAGGUUGAACCUGAGGAAUCCCUUGAACCUGAAGCCUGUUUUACAGAAGACUGUGUACGGAAGUUCAAGUGUUGUCAGAUAAGCAUAGAAGAAGGCAAAGGGAAACUCUGGUGGAAUUUGAGGAAAACAUGCUAUAAGAUAGUGGAGCACAAUUGGUUCGAAACCUUCAUUGUCUUCAUGAUUCUGCUGAGCAGUGGGGCUCUGGCCUUUGAAGAUAUAUACAUUGAGCAGCGAAAAACCAUUAAGACCAUGUUAGAAUAUGCUGACAAGGUUUUCACUUACAUAUUCAUUCUGGAAAUGCUGCUAAAGUGGGUUGCAUAUGGUUUUCAAGUGUAUUUUACCAAUGCCUGGUGCUGGCUAGACUUCCUGAUUGUUGAUGUCUCACUGGUUAGCUUAACUGCAAAUGCCUUGGGUUACUCAGAACUUGGUGCCAUCAAAUCCCUCAGAACACUAAGAGCUCUGAGGCCACUGAGAGCUUUGUCCCGGUUUGAAGGAAUGAGGGUUGUUGUAAAUGCUCUUUUAGGAGCCAUUCCAUCUAUCAUGAAUGUACUUCUGGUUUGUCUGAUCUUUUGGCUAAUAUUCAGUAUCAUGGGAGUGAAUCUCUUUGCUGGCAAGUUUUACCAUUGUAUUAAUUACACCACUGGAGAGAUGUUUGAUGUAAGCGUGGUCAACAACUACAGUGAGUGCAAAGCUCUCAUUGAGAGCAAUCAAACUGCCAGGUGGAAAAAUGUGAAAGUAAACUUUGAUAACGUAGGACUUGGAUAUCUGUCUCUACUUCAAGUAGCCACGUUUAAGGGAUGGAUGGAUAUUAUGUAUGCAGCUGUUGAUUCACGAAAUGUAGAAUUACAACCCAAGUAUGAAGACAACCUGUACAUGUAUCUUUAUUUUGUCAUCUUUAUUAUUUUUGGUUCAUUCUUUACCUUGAAUCUUUUCAUUGGUGUCAUCAUAGAUAACUUCAACCAACAGAAAAAGAAGUUUGGAGGUCAAGACAUUUUUAUGACAGAAGAACAGAAGAAAUACUACAAUGCAAUGAAAAAACUGGGUUCAAAGAAACCACAAAAACCCAUACCUCGACCUGCUAACAAAUUCCAAGGAAUGGUCUUUGAUUUUGUAACCAAACAAGUCUUUGAUAUCAGCAUCAUGAUCCUCAUCUGCCUUAACAUGGUCACCAUGAUGGUGGAAACCGAUGACCAGAGUCAAGAAAUGACAAACAUUCUGUACUGGAUUAAUCUGGUGUUUAUUGUUCUGUUCACUGGAGAAUGUGUGCUGAAACUGAUCUCUCUUCGUUACUACUAUUUCACUAUUGGAUGGAAUAUUUUUGAUUUUGUGGUGGUCAUUCUCUCCAUUGUAGGAAUGUUUCUGGCUGAACUGAUAGAAAAGUAUUUUGUGUCCCCUACCCUGUUCCGAGUGAUCCGUCUUGCCAGGAUUGGCCGAAUCCUACGUCUGAUCAAAGGAGCAAAGGGGAUCCGCACGCUGCUCUUUGCUUUGAUGAUGUCCCUUCCUGCGUUGUUUAACAUCGGCCUCCUUCUUUUCCUGGUCAUGUUCAUCUACGCCAUCUUUGGGAUGUCCAAUUUUGCCUAUGUUAAGAGGGAAGUUGGGAUCGAUGACAUGUUCAACUUUGAGACCUUUGGCAACAGCAUGAUCUGCCUGUUCCAAAUUACAACCUCUGCUGGCUGGGAUGGAUUGCUAGCACCUAUUCUUAAUAGUGGACCUCCAGACUGUGACCCUGACAAAGAUCACCCUGGAAGCUCAGUUAAAGGAGACUGUGGGAACCCAUCUGUUGGGAUUUUCUUUUUUGUCAGUUACAUCAUCAUAUCCUUCCUGGUUGUGGUGAACAUGUACAUCGCGGUCAUCCUGGAGAACUUCAGUGUUGCUACUGAAGAAAGUGCAGAGCCUCUGAGUGAGGAUGACUUUGAGAUGUUCUAUGAGGUUUGGGAGAAGUUUGAUCCCGAUGCGACCCAGUUUAUAGAGUUUGCCAAACUUUCUGAUUUUGCAGAUGCCCUGGAUCCUCCUCUUCUCAUAGCAAAACCCAACAAAGUCCAGCUCAUUGCCAUGGAUCUGCCCAUGGUGAGUGGUGACCGGAUCCACUGUCUUGACAUCUUAUUUGCUUUUACAAAGCGUGUUUUGGGUGAGAGUGGAGAGAUGGAUGCCCUUCGAAUACAGAUGGAAGAGCGAUUCAUGGCAUCAAACCCCUCCAAAGUCUCUUAUGAGCCCAUUACGACCACGUUGAAACGCAAACAAGAGGAGGUGUCUGCUAUUAUUAUCCAGAGGGCUUACAGACGCUACCUCUUGAAGCAAAAAGUUAAAAAGGUAUCAAGUAUAUACAAGAAAGACAAAGGCAAAGAAUGUGAUGGAACACCCAUCAAAGAAGAUACUCUCAUUGAUAAACUGAAUGAGAAUUCAACUCCAGAGAAAACCGAUAUGACGCCUUCCACCACGUCUCCACCCUCGUAUGAUAGUGUGACCAAACCAGAAAAAGAAAAAUUUGAAAAAGACAAAUCAGAAAAGGAAGACAAAGGGAAAGAUAUCAGGGAAAGUAAAAAGUAAAAAGAAACCAAGAAUUUUCCAUUUUGUGAUCAAUUGUUUACAGCCCGUGAUGGUGAUGUGUUUGUGUCAACAGGACUCCCACAGGAGGUCUAUGCCAAACUGACUGUUUUUACAAAUGUAUACUUAAGGUCAGUGCCUAUAACAAGACAGAGACCUCUGGUCAGCAAACUGGAACUCAGUAAACUGGAGAAAUAGUAUCGAUGGGAGGUUUCUAUUUUCACAACCAGCUGACACUGCUGAAGAGCAGAGGCGUAAUGGCUACUCAGACGAUAGGAACCAAUUUAAAGGGGGGAGGGAAGUUAAAUUUUUAUGUAAAUUCAACAUGUGACACUUGAUAAUAGUAAUUGUCACCAGUGUUUAUGUUUUAACUGCCACACCUGCCAUAUUUUUACAAAACGUGUGCUGUGAAUUUAUCACUUUUCUUUUUAAUUCACAGGUUGUUUACUAUUAUAUGUGACUAUUUUUGUAAAUGGGUUUGUGUUUGGGGAGAGGGAUUAAAGGGAGGGAAUUCUACAUUUCUCUAUUGUAUUGUAUAACUGGAUAUAUUUUAAAUGGAGGCAUGCUGCAAUUCUCAUUCACACAUAAAAAAAUCACAUCACAAAAGGGAAGAGUUUACUUCUUGUUUCAGGAUGUUUUUAGAUUUUUGAGGUGCUUAAAUAGCUAUUCGUAUUUUUAAGGUGUCUCAUCCAGAAAAAAUUUAAUGUGCCUGUAAAUGUUCCAUAGAAUCACAAGCAUUAAAGAGUUGUUUUAUUUUUACAUAACCCAUUAAAUGUACAUGUAUAUAUGUAUAUAUGUAUAUGUGCGUGUAUAUACAUAUAUAUGUAUACACACAUGCACACACAGAGAUAUACACAUACCAUUACAUUGUCAUUCACAGUCCCAGCAGCAUGACUAUCACAUUUUUGAUAAGUGUCCUUUGGCAUAAAAUAAAAAUAUCCUAUCAGUCCUUUCUAAGAAGCCUGAAUUGACCAAAAAACAUCCCCACCACCACUUUAUAAAGUUGAUUCUGCUUUAUCCUGCAGUAUUGUUUAGCCAUCUUCUGCUCUUGGUAAGGUUGACAUAGUAUAUGUCAAUUUAAAAAAUAAAAGUCUGCUUUGUAAAUAGUAAUUUUACCCAGUGGUGCAUGUUUGAGCAAACAAAAAUGAUGAUUUAAGCACACUACUUAUUGCAUCAAAUAUGUACCACAGUAAGUAUAGUUUGCAAGCUUUCAACAGGUAAUAUGAUGUAAUUGGUUCCAUUAUAGUUUGAAGCUGUCACUGCUGCAUGUUUAUCUUGCCUAUGCUGCUGUAUCUUAUUCCUUCCACUGUUCAGAAGUCUAAUAUGGGAAGCCAUAUAUCAGUGGUAAAGUGAAGCAAAUUGUUCUACCAAGACCUCAUUCUUCAUGUCAUUAAGCAAUAGGUUGCAGCAAACAAGGAAGAGCUUCUUGCUUUUUAUUCUUCCAACCUUAAUUGAACACUCAAUGAUGAAAAGCCCGACUGUACAAACAUGUUGCAAGCUGCUUAAAUCUGUUUAAAAUAUAUGGUUAGAGUUUUCUAAGAAAAUAUAAAUACUGUAAAAAGUUCAUUUUAUUUUAUUUUUCAGCCUUUUGUACGUAAAAUGAGAAAUUAAAAGUAUCUUCAGGUGGAUGUCACAGUCACUAUUGUUAGUUUCUGUUCCUAGCACUUUUAAAUUGAAGCACUUCACAAAAUAAGAAGCAAGGACUAGGAUGCAGUGUAGGUUUCUGCUUUUUUAUUAGUACUGUAAACUUGCACACAUUUCAAUGUGAAACAAAUCUCAAACUGAGUUCAAUGUUUAUUUGCUUUCAAUAGUAAUGCCUUAUCAUUGAAAGAGGCUUAAAGAAAAAAAAAAUCAGCUGAUACUCUUGGCAUUGCUUGAAUCCAAUGUUUCCACCUAGUCUUUUUAUUCAGUAAUCAUCAGUCUUUUCCAAUGUUUGUUUACACAGAUAGAUCUUAUUGACCCAUAUGGCACUAGAACUGUAUCAGAUAUAAUAUGGGAUCCCAGCUUUUUUUCCUCUCCCACAAAACCAGGUAGUGAAGUUAUAUUACCAGUUACAGCAAAAUACUUUGUGUUUCACAAGCAACAAUAAAUGUAGAUUCUUUAUACUGAAGCUAUUGACUUGUAGUGUGUUGGUGAAAUGCAUGCAGGAAAAUGCUGUUACCAUAAAGAACGGUAAACCACAUUACAAUCAAGCCAAAAGAAUAAAGGUUUCGCUUUUGUUUUUGUAUUUAAUUGUUGUCUUUGUUUCUAUCUUUGAAAUGCCAUUUAAAGGUAGAUUUCUAUCAUGUAAAAAUAAUCUAUCUGAAAAACAAAUGUAAAGAACACACAUUAAUUACUAUAAUUCAUCUUUCAAUUUUUUCAUGGAAUGGAAGUUAAUUAAGAAGAGUGUAUUGGAUAACUACUUUAAUAUUGGCCAAAAAGCUAGAUAUGGCAUCAGGUAGACUAGUGGAAAGUUACAAAAAUUAAUAAAAAAUUGACUAACA